AAAUUCAGAAUCACACUUGGUAACUAAUAAUGAAAGAUUUCAAACCCCAAACAGUGCAACUGAAACUUUUGCAUUACUAUACUACUGAGAAUAUCUAACAUGUUGUUACUAAUCAAUGUCAUUCUGACCUUGUGGGUUUCCUGUGCUAAUGGACAAGAAGUGAAACCUUGUGAUUUUCCAGAAAUUCAACAUGGAGGUCUAUAUUAUAAGAGUUUGCGUAGACUAUACUUUCCAGCAGCUGCAGGACAAUCUUAUUCCUAUUACUGUGAUCAAAAUUUUGUGACUCCUUCAGGAAGUUACUGGGAUUACAUUCAUUGCACACAAGAUGGUUGGUCACCAACGGUCCCAUGCCUCAGAACAUGCUCAAAAUCAGAUGUAGAAAUUGAAAAUGGAUUCAUUUCUGAAUCUUCCUCUAUUUAUAUUUUAAAUGAAGAAACACAAUAUAAUUGUAAACCAGGAUAUGCAACAGCAGAGGGAAAUUCUUCAGGAUCAAUUACAUGUUUGCAAAAUGGAUGGUCAACACAACCAAUUUGCAUUAAAUUUUGUGAUAUGCCUGUUUUUGAGAAUUCCAGAGCCAAGAGUAAUGGCAUGUGGUUUAAGCUCCAUGACACAUUGGACUAUGAAUGCUAUGAUGGAUAUGAAAGCAGUUAUGGAAACACCACAGAUUCCAUAGUGUGUGGUGAAGAUGGCUGGUCCCAUUUGCCAACAUGCUAUAAUUCUUCAGAAAACUGUGGGCCUCCUCCACCUAUUAGCAAUGGAGAUACCACGUCCUUCCCGCAAAAAGUGUAUCUGCCAUGGUCAAGAGUCGAGUACCAGUGCCAGUCCUACUAUGAACUUCAGGGUUCUAAAUAUGUAACAUGUAGUAAUGGAGACUGGUCAGAACCACCAAGAUGCAUAUCAAUGAAACCUUGUGAGUUUCCAGAAAUUCAACAUGGACAUCUAUAUUAUGAGAAUACGCGUAGACCAUACUUUCCAGUAGCUACAGGACAAUCUUACUCCUAUUACUGUGACCAAAAUUUUGUGACUCCUUCAGGAAGUUACUGGGAUUACAUUCACUGCACACAAGAUGGGUGGUUGCCAACAGUCCCAUGCCUCAGAACAUGCUCAAAAUCAGAUAUAGAAAUUGAAAAUGGAUUCAUUUCUGAAUCUUCCUCUAUUUAUAUUUUAAAUAAAGAAAUACAAUAUAAAUGUAAACCAGGAUAUGCAACAGCAGAUGGAAAUUCUUCAGGUUCAAUUACAUGUUUGCAAAAUGGAUGGUCAGCACAACCAAUUUGCAUUAAAUUUUGUGAUAUGCCUGUUUUUGAGAAUUCCAGAGCCAAGAGUAAUGGCAUGCGGUUUAAGCUCCAUGACACAUUGGACUACGAAUGCUACGAUGGAUAUGAAAUCAGUUAUGGAAACACCACAGGUUCCAUAGUGUGUGGUGAAGAUGGGUGGUCCCAUUUCCCAACAUGUUAUAAUUCUUCAGAAAAGUGUGGGCCUCCUCCACCUAUUAGCAAUGGUGAUACCACCUCCUUUCUACUAAAAGUGUAUGUGCCACAGUCAAGAGUCGAGUACCAAUGCCAGUCCUACUAUGAACUUCAGGGUUCUAAUUAUGUAACAUGUAGUAAUGGAGAGUGGUCGGAACCACCAAGAUGCAUACGUAUCCACUUCUGUAGAUGAUCAUGUCCAAGUUUGAGCUCCAAACUAUGCAAGUGGCAAGACUGAAGAAGAAAUUAGUAUCCUCAAAUCAAAAUAGUUUACAAGUAUCUUCAAACUUGAUUUCAUAGAAAAGUGUUAGGUUUCAGAGAUAAAUUCUGAGUCUCAAAUUUGAUUGAAUGGGGAGAUGGACACUCCUAAGAUGGGUUUCACAGCAAAAGCAUUACCUCUUCUCACAAUCAAGAACAGGAAAGGAUUAUAAUUAUCUGAAGAUACAAGAUCAGUUCCAUGAUACAAGCAAGACUUUCAGUCUUCAAAACUAAAGAAGCAAAGAGCAUUCAAGCACAGAAUUCUAGGGAAAAAGGCAACCUUAUGGAAAAGAUUACAUAUACAUAUGGCAUAUUAAAGCAAUGAGGAAAACUUUCCCAGGCAGCAGGAAACUUUAGAAAGUUUUGGAAAAUAUGUUUGGAGAAGUAUUUAGAGUUCAAAUAAUAUUUAUUUUUGAAUUGUAAACAGCCUCUGAAUGUAUUGAAGAGCUCUUAAAAUUUUUUGGAUCUCAAAAGUGAUAUGUACUAUGUUAAGAAAUUUAUUUAAGUAAGUACUUGAAAGAUGUAUUAAAAUAUGAUUGGGGAAAUUUCUAAAGAAAUGCUAAUGCUAAUAAGGGCUAAACUAGAAUGCAGAAUACUUGAGUCAAAAGAAGAGAUAGGUGAGUGAAUGAUAUCAUCAAAAAUGAAAAGCUUGCUAUGUAAGAACUGACAUUUUUAUCAUGUAAGAAUUAGGCUUAAUACCUAGGGUAUGGGUUGAUAGGUACAGCAAACCACCAUGGCACACAUUUACCUAUGGAACAAACCUGCACAUCCUGCACAUGUACCCUGGAACUUAAAAAAAAAUUAUAAAUUUUUUUACAAAAGAAUUUUAUAAAAGAAAACCCAUAUGUGGAAGUAACAUUAUCUUACUGAUUUUACAGAUGAAGGCAUAGUGAGAUAGAGUAAUUUGUCCAUAAUCAUGUAGGGAUUCACAUUAACUCCUGUGUGCUUAUCCUUGCCUCUUUAAAAUAGAAAAUGAAGAUGACAGGGAUAGAUGAUGGUGAUAGAGAGAGAGAUAAUUGACAGAUAUUGAGGUGUAUGUAUGUAUGUAUGUAUGUAUGUAUAUAUAGAGAGUUUUAUUUUAAUAGAUGACUAUUAGAAAGAUUAUACCUUUCUACAGUUCUUUUUCUACACUGUGGGCAUAAGAGAAAAAUAUAAACAUAGAAUUAAAUUAGCAAAAUGUGAGUACAUUUGGAGUGCUUGUAGUCACGGCUUGUCAAAUGGGGGAAAGGAGGAUAAGUAACCAUGACUCCAGUGGAACAUGUUAGCAUAAUCCUUUUUGAUAUGAAGUCACUAGGGUGGACACAACAUGUUUUAGGGAAGAAGAGUUCAGGCUCUAGAGAAAGACUGCCAGGGUUCACGUUUAUCACCUCACCUGAUGAUCUCUGCUGUGACGUUGGGGAAGUGCAACUGAACUUAUUAUAUUUUUGAAAUGCUAAAGUCAGUAUGUAGCACAAAUUAAUAACUAUUAACUAUUUGGAUUAUUUUAUAAUUUUAUUUUAUCCUAAACUACUCAUUAGGAUGCAUUUUAUUUGCUCAUGAAAGGCAAGAUUAUGAUUGUUAAUUGUUUCUUUUUCUGCUUUCAGAUCCAUGUAUAAUAACUGAAGAAAACAUGAA